GAGAUCAAAGGGCGUCGCCCAAAGCGGGACAGGUCCAGCGGUUGUUCUGUGUGAAGUCGCGCGGCUUCCACCCACGCAGUGUUCUAAGUGAAGGCCAGAAACUCGCUCGCCAUGUCGGCUGCAGAGGCGGGGGGUGUUUUCCACAGAGCCAGGGGCAGGACCCUGGCCGCGUUUCCCGCAGAAAAGGAAAGCGAAUGGAAAGGCCCAUUCUACUUCAUCCUGGGCGCAGACCCACAGUUUGGGCUGAUCAAGGCCUGGUCCACUGGGGACUGUGACAAUGGCGGUGACGAAUGGGAACAGGAGAUCCGUCUAACUGAGCAAGCCGUCCAGGCCAUCAACAAGCUGAACCCCAAACCCAAAUUCUUCGUUCUGUGCGGCGACCUCAUCCACGCCAUGCCAGGGAAGCCGUGGCGGACGGAGCAGACGGAGGACCUGAAGCGAGUGCUUAGGGCAGUGGACAGGGCCAUCCCACUGGUCCUUGUCAGCGGCAACCAUGACAUUGGCAACACCCCCACGGCCGAGACCGUCGAGGAGUUCUGCCGGACUUGGGGAGAUGACUACUUCAGCUUCUGGGUCGGGGGCGUCCUGUUCCUGGUCCUCAACUCCCAGUUCUACGAGAACCCCUCCAAAUGCCCCAGCCUGAAGCAGGCUCAGGACCAGUGGCUGGACGAGCAGCUGAGCAUCGCGAGGCAGCGGCACUGCCAGCAUGCCAUCGUCUUCCAGCACAUCCCGCUGUUCCUGGAGAGCAUCGACGAGGACGACGACUACUACUUCAACCUCAGCAAGUCCACUCGGAAGAAGUUGGCAGACAAGUUCAUCCACGCAGGUGUCAAAGUCGUGUUCUCAGGCCACUACCACAGGAAUGCCGGGGGUACCUACCAGAACCUCGACAUGGUGGUGUCAUCUGCCAUUGGAUGCCAGCUGGGCAGAGACCCCCACGGGCUCCGAGUCGUGGUGGUCACCGCCGAGAAAAUUGUUCACCGAUACUACAGUCUAGAUGAGCUGAGUGAGAAAGGAAUAGAAGACGAUCUCAUGGAUUUGAUCAAGAAAAAAUGACGCUCCUUCCCGUUCCCGUUCACUUUUCACUUGCACUAUUUUUUUAUUUUGCCAGAAACAGCAGCUGCACACAACCUCUUGCUGAAAUAUAAAAAUAGCCCAGGCAGGUUUGUGAAUUUAUGUCCUUUUGCAUAAAUCAGAGAGCUGGGGCCCUGUCCUGAAUUAUAUUCAAAAUAGAACUGCAUUUCCUUUAAAAUGGAGCGAAUGAUCCUGGAAAUCAGUUUUUAAAAUAUUAGACUAUCUCUGCAUGGAUGUUUGAAUAAAUUCUCCUAAUGCUGUGUUUCUCAACUCCACUUUUGAAUUGGAUUGUAUUCUGGUUAGCAUAUGGUCAAAGUCUGCCUAUCGACCUCAAUUCCAAUCUGACAGCCAAGUAUGAUCUUUGAUAAUUCCUUAAACAAACUACACCUGAUUGUAUUAAAUUGUGGUCACGAUUCCCAAAACGCUAGGCAAAACAAAGUUCAUCUCCUUUCCUUUCCAGCGGAACGAACAGCUGUCUCCCUUGUUGUGAGAGCCAUGCAGACUUAUUUUGACAAGGAGCCAAGUAGGCACCAUUUACUGUUCAAUUCUGAGACUUCUGAUGAUAGGAACAGAAUGCAGUUGAUACAGCUCGGAGCUUAAAUUUGCCUUCCUGGGUGCCUAGAAAAGUCACCUUUGCACAUAAAUUGGCCAUUUCUGAAAAUCUCCUCCAAGAGACUGAAACCAAAGCUCUAAAACGCCGCUUCUUCAGUCUCUGGGGAGCACGUUGAGUUGGUUCACAUCCACAUUCUGGCUGUGUAGCCACUCCACAGAUGGGUGGUCUCUUGGGAUCAGAAUGCCCCUCCACUCAUGAGACUCUUCAUUUUGUCCACUUUGACAGGAAAAGUGGGAAUGUAUGCAGAGCUCUCAAAAGAAACAAAAAAGGCCAAAACGGUGCCUUCAGCCACAUCCUCUGAAUUGGCCCUGACUUGGACUAAAUGCACUAAUGCAAAAUCCCUUGACAAAAGCGCAUAGGUUAUUUCAAACCAGCAUUGUUUUUUAUGUAACCUGUUUUACCGCAUCUUCUCAGCAGCUUCUGACCACUGCUCAAUUUUCUCCUUUACAGCCAUUGUUCUGGUGGACAAAUAACCUAGGUACUCCAAAUCCUGGCAGGAAAAAUAUACAGCAUUAUGAAACAGCACUCAGUAAUCCUAAAAUGAUUUCCAAAGCUGGUUACACAUGACCUGCAAAGUCUAUUAAAUUAAAAGACUUUCUCAUUACAGAGUUUAGUCAACGUAGCAAAACCAUGGGAAAUUAAAUGGAAAGAUAAUUAAAUAUGUAAAUUCAUAAGGAACAAAAGACGAGAAGUUAAUUAUACAAUAGGCUGGUGACACCAGAGUUCAUUGUUAUGUGCCACAAGAAAAUUAAAUUUUUUAAAAAACUAGAACGCUCUUCUUUUAGUGUUUUGCUGAAAUCCUGUUUUGUAUUUGUUUCUUUACAACAGGUGUAGGUAUAGGAGGUCAAGAAAAGGAGUUCGGUAAAGGGCAUAGCUAAUAACAACCACACAUUGGGCCAGGCACAGUGGCUUACGCCUGUAAUCCCAGCACUUUGGGAGGCUGAGACGGGCAGAUCACCUGAGAUCAGGAGUUUGAGAACAGCCUGGCCAACAUGGUGAAACUCCAUCUCUACUAAAAAUACAAAAAUUAGCCAGGCAUGCUGGUGCACACCUGUAAUCCCAGCUACUCGGGAGGCUGAGGCAGGAGAUCGCUGGAACUCAGGAGGCAGAGGUUGCAGUGAGCCAAGAUCAUGCCACUGCACUCCAGCCUGGGCAACAGAGCAAGACUCUGUCUCAAAAAAAAAAAAAAAAAACCACACACACACACAUUGAGACUUGAGAUGUGGUGACACUUGGAUCAUAAACAGAGGGCUUCGAUUCCAGGAUGGGGGUUCCUCCAGGGGGAAAUGAAAAGGAGCUCUCACUCUGUUCUUACGUAUGCACAAUGCUCUGAAUUGUGGCACAUGGGUUUGCAGAAGGAUAAUGGAGAUAAUUGAAAGUAAUGAAAAUGAAACCAAAUCUCCUUCCCCAAAAACUUAAAAGAACUGAUUCAAAAGUACCCCAAGAAUAUGCAAAGAAAAGGGAAUCACAUCAACAGAUGAUUGGAUAAAGAACAUGUGGUAUGUAUACAUAAUGGAAUACUAUUCAGCCACUAAAAAGAAUGAAACCAUGUCUUUUGCAGCAACCUGGAUGGAACUGGAGGCUGUUAUCUUAAGUGAAAUAACUUAGAAGUAGAAAGUCGAAUACUUCAUGUUCUCACUCAUAAAUGGGAGCUACAUAAAGUGUACCCAUGAACAUAGAGUGUGGAACAAACAUUGGAGACUCAGAAGGGUGGGAGGAGGGUAAGGGAUGAGAAAGUACCUGAUGGGUACAGUGUACACUUUUCUGGUGUUGGUUGCAGGAAAAGCCUGGACUUCACCACUUCGCAAUAUAUCCGUGUAACAAAACUGCACUUGUACGCCUUAUAUUUAUACAAAUUUAAUUUUUUAAAAGGGAAGAGAGAAUCAUAUUAAUUUCUCACCACUUUUUAAGUAAGCAAACAGCAGUAUUUCCCAGAGGCAAGAGGUUCAGCAAGAAGUCAGGAAAUGUUUUUGUAGAUAAGCAUCUAUCAUUCUGAUGGGCCAUGACUAGUGUGUUCACUUGUAAUUCCUUUGCCUUUAAAAAAAGAGAAUGAUAUCAAAAAAUAAGUGCCUUAUACUGUGAAAAACGAUAAAAGGACUUCCUGAUUCUAAGUGCUAUGGUUUUGAAUGUUUAUUAUGUGUUUUAAGUGCUUUGGCUCAGAAAGGUGGGGGUCACGUGGCCAAGGUCGCCUAACUCAUCUUGGUGGAGAAAGAACGGAUGUAGAUGGCCCAAGGCUUGAGUCCAUGCUCCAUAACACUGUCCUGUCUUGGAAAACGUUUCUCAGAGGUGAAAGGUUGCACCAGCUCAGCCAGUGGCAACACACUGAGUACGGUAUUCAGCACCUUGGACAGCGUUAGCUGGAGGCCCAGGGAUUUCCUCCCAGCUCUGCAAAGCCUAGACCAGACCCUGAUUGCACCAGGUUCAGGGGGCAGAAGCUUGUCCAAAGAGCAGAUGGUUCCAGGGGGAGGAUUUUUACUGGGGGAGAUUUAGAAACCGAACUGAACCAUAAUGAGUCACGGGACACAGCCCUGUCUGCAGCAGUAACUGUCCGCAGCUCUAGCUGCUCCAUGUCUGGAGUUACCACCACAGGGUGUAGGAAACCACCAGCUGUCUCAAGGCAAGGAAUGUCACCUAAUGCUCCCCUUUCCAAUUAAUCACUUUAAUUGGAGGAAAAAACAAAAACACAAGGACAUGUUACGGGGGAAGGUUUUUUAAAGUGAUCUCAAAUUGGAUUGCAAAGGCUCAAGUGACUUUGGGAAUGGGGCUGGGGAGAUGAUCAUUUACUUUUUACAAUAAAUAAUUUUAUCUCACAUCUUUAGUCAAGUUUCUCCUAAGUUUGGGGAGAAUGGGGAAAAAAUGUAGUAAGCUUUAUGGGACUAGCAACAGAACGUUUUAUCCUAUUUUGUGAUUUUCAGUAUUAAGAGAUUAUUGAUCACUUGCAGAGUUACAAGGCAAGCACUAGUUUAAAUCUGAAUUAGACUAGGGCCAUUGACCUUAUAUACCUGUAAAAGACACUACGGUGUAUACAACUGUAGAAACAAUAUACACAUAGUAGUUUAAUAUUACAGUCUGUAUUCCAAUGCAGAAUCUUUUGAGAAAAGGUUGCCAAAACAUCAUUUGCAUUUACUUGAACCCUUUUUUAGACAGAAUCUUGCUCUAUCACCCAGGCUGGAGUGCAGUGGUGUGAUCACAGCUCACUGCAGCCUUGAACUCUUGGGCUCAACCAACCUUCCCACCUCAGCCUCCCAAAUUAGCUGGGACUAUAGGCUCGUGUCACCACAUCUAAUUUUUUAUUUUUAUAUUUGUGGAGUUGAAGGUCUUGCUCUGUUACCCAGGCUGGUCUUGAACUCCUGGCCCCAAGCAGUCCUUCCACCUUGGCCUCCCAAAGUGUUGGGAUUACAGGCGUUGGCCACUGUACCCAGCCUUACUUGAACUCUUAAUACUUAUUCCCAAGUGGUACCUAAAAUGGUUUUGUGCAGUCACAAUAUUAGGUAGCAAUAUUAUAUUGAGCUGGAGGAAAAAGAAGAUUUAGGAGUAAAUUGCCAAGGCAAGUUCUGUUAAAAGCUUUCUGUAAUAGACAUCAGGGAUUUUUUUUAUUCAGGUAACCUCAACAGUUUUGAUUGCACAUGUAACAUAGUACUUGACAGGUAAUACUGAUUUUUAUAACUUCAUAAAAUAUUCUCAAGCCAUGGAGGAGCUCUUAUGUAUUUUUUAAUGAGUACACACACACACACACACACACACACACACACACACAUAUAGUAAAAGUGGAGGAUUCUUUUCUUGGAAUAAUGAUUUCUAGCAUUUAUCUAGAAAAGAUUUUGCUGACUAAAUUUUCCUUUUCCUCCAGUGGAUUUUUAAACAUCAGUGCAUGCACAUAAAUACAGAUUGGAUUUUUCCUUUAGGCUUUAUCUAUGUAAAUGAAGUCGAUUAAAUGUGAAUAAUCAUGUUACCCUUCAUUAUUCUGACCAUUAUGUUUGAGAAGUAGAUUUCUUCACUAAAGGGGCUUUGCAGCACACUUAGAAUGAGUGAGCCACUGUGCCUCUCUAGAAACUGGCUUCUUGUCAUCAUUUCAACAUCCACUCAAACGCUCACCCCUGAAAGUGGCCUUCCUGCUUGAUAUGGUUUGGCUCUGUGUCUCCACCCAAAUUGGUUUGGCUCUGUGUCCCCACUGAAAUCUCAUCUCGAAUUGUAAUCCCCAUAAUCCCCAUGUGUCAAGGGACGGACCUGGUGGGAGGUAAUUGGAUCAUGGAGGCAGUUUCUCCCAUGCUAUUCUUGUGAUAGUGAGUUCUCAUGACACUGAUGGUUUUGUGUUUGAUAGCUCCUUCACACUCUUUCUUUCCUGUUGCCAUGUAAGACAUGCCUGCUUCCCCUUCCACCAGGAUUGUAAGUUUCCUGAGGCCUCCCCAGCCAUGCGGAACUGUGAGUCUAUUAAAUCUCUUUUCUUUGUAAAUUA